GGGAGAACCCACAGGGAGACCCACAGACACAUAUGCACGAGAGAGACAGAGGAGGAAAGAGACAGAGACAAAGGCACAGCGGAAGAAGGCAGAGACAGGGCAGGCACAGAAGCGGCCCAGACAGAGUCCUACAGAGGGAGAGGCCAGAGAAGCUGCAGAAGACACAGGCAGGGAGAGACAAAGAUCCAGGAAAGGAGGGCUCAGGAGGAGAGUUUGGAGAAGCCAGACCCCUGGGCACCUCUCCCAAGCCCAAGGACUAAGUUUUCUCCAUUUCCUUUAACGGUCCUCAGCCCUUCUGAAAACUUUGCCUCUGACCUUGGCAGGAGUCCAAGCCCCCAGGCUACAGAGAGGAGCUUUCCAAAGCUAGGGUGUGGAGGACUUGGUGCCCUAGACGGCCUCAGUCCCUCCCAGCUGCAGUACCAGUGCCAUGUCCCAGACAGGCUCGCAUCCCGGGAGGGGCUUGGCAGGGCGCUGGCUGUGGGGAGCCCAACCCUGCCUCCUGCUCCCCAUUGUGCCGCUCUCCUGGCUGGUGUGGCUGCUUCUGCUACUGCUGGCCUCUCUCCUGCCCUCAGCCCGGCUGGCCAGCCCCCUCCCCCGGGAGGAGGAGAUCGUGUUUCCAGAGAAGCUCAACGGCAGCGUCCUGCCUGGCUCGGGCGCCCCUGCCAGGCUGUUGUGCCGCUUGCAGGCCUUUGGGGAGACGCUGCUACUAGAGCUGGAGCAGGACUCCGGUGUGCAGGUCGAGGGGCUGACAGUGCAGUACCUGGGCCAGGCGCCUGAGCUGCUGGGUGGAGCAGAGCCUGGCACCUACCUGACUGGCACCAUCAAUGGAGAUCCGGAGUCGGUGGCAUCUCUGCACUGGGAUGGGGGAGCCCUGUUAGGCGUGUUACAAUAUCGGGGGGCUGAACUCCACCUCCAGCCCCUGGAGGGAGGCACCCCUAACUCUGCUGGGGGACCUGGGGCUCACAUCCUACGCCGGAAGAGUCCUGCCAGCGGUCAAGGUCCCAUGUGCAACGUCAAGGCUCCUCUUGGAAGCCCCAGCCCCAGACCCCGAAGAGCCAAGCGCUUUGCUUCACUGAGUAGAUUUGUGGAGACACUGGUGGUGGCAGAUGACAAGAUGGCCGCAUUCCACGGUGCGGGGCUAAAGCGCUACCUGCUAACAGUGAUGGCAGCAGCAGCCAAGGCCUUCAAGCACCCAAGCAUCCGCAAUCCUGUCAGCUUGGUGGUGACUCGGCUAGUGAUCCUGGGGUCAGGCGAGGAGGGGCCCCAAGUGGGGCCCAGUGCUGCCCAGACCCUGCGCAGCUUCUGUGCCUGGCAGCGGGGCCUCAACACCCCUGAGGACUCGGACCCUGACCACUUUGACACAGCCAUUCUGUUUACCCGUCAGGACCUGUGUGGAGUCUCCACUUGCGACACGCUGGGUAUGGCUGAUGUGGGCACCGUCUGUGACCCGGCUCGGAGCUGUGCCAUUGUGGAGGAUGAUGGGCUCCAGUCAGCCUUCACUGCUGCUCAUGAACUGGGUCAUGUCUUCAACAUGCUCCAUGACAACUCCAAGCCAUGCAUCAGUUUGAAUGGGCCUUUGAGCACCUCUCGCCAUGUCAUGGCCCCUGUGAUGGCUCAUGUGGAUCCUGAGGAGCCCUGGUCCCCCUGCAGUGCCCGCUUCAUCACUGACUUCCUGGACAAUGGCUAUGGGCACUGUCUCUUAGACAAACCAGAGGCUCCAUUGCAUCUGCCUGUGACUUUCCCUGGCAAGGACUAUGAUGCUGACCGCCAGUGCCAGCUGACCUUCGGGCCCGACUCACGCCAUUGUCCACAGCUGCCGCCGCCCUGUGCUGCCCUCUGGUGCUCUGGCCACCUCAAUGGCCAUGCCAUGUGCCAGACCAAACACUCGCCCUGGGCCGAUGGCACACCCUGCGGGCCCGCACAGGCCUGCAUGGGUGGUCGCUGCCUCCACAUGGACCAGCUCCAGGACUUCAAUAUUCCACAGGCUGGUGGCUGGGGUCCUUGGGGACCAUGGGGUGACUGCUCUCGGACCUGUGGGGGUGGUGUCCAGUUCUCCUCCCGAGACUGCACGAGGCCUGUCCCCCGGAAUGGUGGCAAGUACUGUGAGGGCCGCCGUACCCGCUUCCGCUCCUGCAACACUGAGGACUGCCCAACUGGCUCAGCCCUGACCUUCCGCGAGGAGCAGUGUGCUGCCUACAACCACCGCACCGACCUCUUCAAGAGCUUCCCAGGGCCCAUGGACUGGGUUCCUCGCUACACAGGCGUGGCCCCCCAGGACCAGUGCAAACUCACCUGCCAGGCCCAGGCACUGGGCUACUACUAUGUGCUGGAGCCACGGGUGGUAGAUGGGACCCCCUGUUCCCCGGACAGCUCCUCGGUCUGUGUCCAGGGCCGAUGCAUCCAUGCUGGCUGUGAUCGCAUCAUUGGCUCCAAGAAGAAGUUUGACAAGUGCAUGGUGUGCGGAGGGGACGGUUCUGGUUGCAGCAAGCAGUCAGGCUCCUUCAGGAAAUUCAGGUACGGAUACAACAAUGUGGUCACUAUCCCCGCGGGGGCCACCCACAUUCUUGUCCGGCAGCAGGGAAACCCUGGCCACCGGAGCAUCUACUUGGCCCUGAAGCUGCCAGAUGGCUCCUAUGCCCUCAAUGGUGAAUACACGCUGAUGCCCUCCCCCACAGAUGUGGUACUGCCUGGGGCAGUCAGCUUGCGCUACAGCGGGGCCACUGCAGCCUCAGAGACACUGUCAGGCCAUGGGCCACUGGCCCAGCCUUUGACACUGCAAGUCCUAGUGGCUGGCAACCCCCAGGACACACGCCUCCGAUACAGCUUCUUCGUGCCCCGGCCGACCCCUUCAACGCCACGCCCCACUCCCCAGGACUGGCUGCACCGAAGAGCACAGAUUCUGGAGAUCCUUCGGCGGCGCCCCUGGGCGGGCAGGAAAUAACCUCACUAUCCCGGCUGCCCUUUCUGGGCACCGGGGCCUCGGACUUAGCUGGGAGAAAGAGAGAGCUUCUGUUGCUGCCUCAUGCUAAGACUCAGUGGGGAGGGGCUGUGGGCGUGAGACCUGCCCCUCCUCUCUGCCCUAAUGCGCAGGCUGGCCCUGCCCUGGUUUCCUGCCCUGGGAGGCAGUGAUGGGUUAGUGGAUGGAAGGGGCUGACAGACAGCCCUCCAUCUAAACUGCCCCCUCUGCCCUGCGGGUCACAGGAGGGAGGGGGAAGGCAGGGAGGGCCUGGGCCCCAGUUGUAUUUAUUUAGUAUUUAUUCACUUUUAUUUAGCACCAGGGAAGGGGACAAGGACUAGGGUCCUGGGGAACCUGACCCCUGACCCCUCAUAGCCCUCACCCUGGGGCUAGGAAAUCCAGGGUGGUGGUGAUAGGUAUAAGUGGUGUGUGUAUGCGUGUGUGUGUGUGUGAAAAUGUGUGUGUGCUUAUGUAUGAGGUACAACCUGUUCUGCUUUCCUCUUCCUGAAUUUUAUUUUUUGGGAAAAGAAAAGUCAAGGGUAGGGUGGGCCUUCAGGGAGUGAGGGAUUAUCUUUUUUUUUUUUUCUUUCUUUCUUUCUUUUUUUUUUUUGAGACAGAAUCUCGCUCUGUCGCCCAGGCUGGAGUGCAAUGGCACAAUCUCGGCUCACUGCAUCCUCCGCCUCCCGGGUUCAAGUGAUUCUCAUGCCUCAGCCUCCUGAGUAGCUGGGAUUACAGGCUCCUGCCACCACGCCCGGCUAAUUUUUGUUUUGUUUUGUUUGGAGACAGAGUCUCGCUAUUGUCACCAGGGCUGGAAUGAUUUCAGCUCACUGCAACCUUCGCCACCUGGGUUCCAGCAAUUCUCCUGCCUCAGCCUCCCGAGUAGCUGAGAUUAUAGGCACCUACCACCACGCCCGGCUAAUUUUUGUAUUUUUAGUAGAGACGGGGUUUCACCAUGUUGGCCAGGCUGGUCUCGAACUCCUGACCUUAGGUGAUCCACUCGCCUUCAUCUCCCAAAGUGCUGGGAUUACAGGCGUGAGCCACCGUGCCUGGCCACGCCCAACUAAUUUUUGUAUUUUUAGUAGAGACAGGGUUUCACCAUGUUGGCCAGGCUGCUCUUGAACUCCUGACCUCAGGUAAUCGACCUGCCUCGGCCUCCCAAAGUGCUGGGAUUACAGGUGUGAGCCACCACGCCCGGUACAUAUUUUUUAAAUUGAAUUCUACUAUUUAUGUGAUCCUUUUGGAGUCAGACAGAUGUGGUUGCAUCCUAACUCCAUGUCUCUGAGCAUUAGAUUUCUCAUUUGCCAAUAAUAAUACCUCCCUUAGAAGUUUGUUGUGAGGAUUAAAUAAUGUAAAUAAAGAACUAGCAUAACACUCAGCAUCUAGUAAGUGCUCAACAAAUAGCAGCUGCUGUUACUUACUGUUAUCAAAUUUCUGUCCACAUCCACUCUCCAUAUGCACUUGAAGGUGGCAAAGAUCCACAACCAUGGUGCCUGCCUUUAUCCUCAGGGUCCGUUCCUUUGGUUGGCAGACCCCUAUCCUGGGUUCUGAGGGACCAACAGAGAAAGGAAAAUUCCAUCCCUCACCUCUGGAAGUUCCCAAUCACAGGAAGGAAACAUAGUAAGCACGUGGCUACAAAUACAAUUGACAAGAACAUGAAGGUGCAGGAUAACAAGAACAAAUAACAAGAACAACUGCAUCAACACAAAUGAGUGCUUAGUAAUAAGGGUGAUAGUUGAGGGGUCUGGGUUUCACAACAGUAGAAAGAGCACUGGAGUGGGAGCCAGCGGGUCUGGAUUCAAUUUGGGGCUCGGCGUCUUAUUAGCUGGGUGGUGUUGGGUAAGUCACUGAUGCUGAGCCUUAGAUUGCUCAUAUGGGACUAACAGUAUCUACUCCCACAGAGUUGUUCUGGGAACAAAUGCUAGAAUAUUUUCAAAAUAGUAAAGGUUAUAGUCAUGGCCAUGUGAGAGGUUACCCCUAUGACUACCUGAAGAUGGAACGGAGUCUCCAGAAUCUGCCAGUGUAAACCCAGCAGAAUGCCUAGAAGAUGUGAGAUUAGAAUAAAAUUUCAUAAAACAAAAACAAUCGGGCACGGUGGCUCAUGCCUGUAAUCCCAGCACUUUGGGAGGCCGAAAUGGGCGGAUCACGAGGUCAGGAGAUUGAGACCGACCAUCCUGGCUACCACAGUGAAACCCCGUGUCUACUAAAAAUACAAAAUAUAUAUAUAUAUAUAUAUAUAUAUUAGCCGGGCAUGGUGACAGGUGCCUAUAGUCCCAGCUACUUGGGAGACUGAGGCAGGAGAAUGACUUGCACCCGGGAGGCAGAGCUUACAGUGAGUCGAGAUUGCGCCACUGCACUCCAGCCUGGGAGACAGAGUGAGACUCGUCUCGAUACAAAAACAAAAACAAAAACAGGAUAUGGUUUGGCAGGAAAUAGGCAAGAAGGCAAAAAGAAUAACCUGGAAAAGGAUCUGAGGUAAGGGAGCCAGGUGCCUCAAAAUGGCAGAAUACCUGAUGCCUGAGGAGAGGGAGGGAAUAAAACAUCUGCAUUUUCCCCUCUGGGCAAGGCGCCUUUGCUUGAGAAAGAAUUUUGGGCUGGAUGAGAUGGUUCACACCUGUAAUCCCAGUACUUUGGCAGGAGGAUUGCUUGAGGCCAGGAGGUUGGGACCAACCUGGGCAACAUAGAAAGAUUCCAUCUCUACCAAAAAAAAAAAAGAUUGAAAAAUUAGCCGGGCGUGGUGGCACCUGUAGUCCCAGCUACUUGGGAGGCUAAAAUAGGAGGACUGCUUGAGCCCACGAUUUCGAGGCUAUGGUGAGCUACAAUCAUGCCACUAUACUCCAGCCUGGGUGAGAGACCAAAACACCAACUCAAAAAAAAAAAAAAAAAAAAAAAAAGGGCCAGGCAUGGUGGCUCACACCUGUAAUCUCAGCACUUUGGGAGGCUGAGGUUCAAAACCAGCCAGGCCAACAUGGUGAAACCCCAUCUCUACUAAAAAAAAAAUACAAAAAAUUAGCCAGGUGUGGUGGCAAGCGCCUAUAGUCCCAGCUACUCAUGAGGCUGAGGCAGGAGGAUCGCUUGAACCUGGGAGGUGGAGGUUGCAGUGAGCCGAAAUUGCGCCAUUGCACUCCAGUCUGGGCGAUAGAGUGAGACUCCAUCUCAAAAAAAAAAAAAAAAAAAAAAAGAACUUGGGCAGUCCUCUAUGUGUCAUGGAUGGAACAGGGAUGGGCAAGGGUGGUAGGUAGACCCUGCAAGAAUUUGGAGUUUUGAGAGGCAGACGCAGGACUGCUAGGGAUUGGGGAAGGUACUGGAUGUGGGGUUGUGGGAGAAACUAUAGGUAAAGAAGACCCUGAGGUUGAGGUGGAAGAGUGAAGAAUGGGGGAACCAAAGGCACUUCACUCUGCCAUAGCAGCCCCUAGCUGGGAUGCCAAAUACUGCUUGGAAUGUGAAGCUGGGACUAUGGGGUUGAGGCAGGCCAUGGAGGUUGUAGUGGUUAUAUGUGCUAUGCUUACUGGAUCUGGGCUUUGCUAAUCAAGUUCUGUACCAGGCAGUGCCUUAUACAGCACCCUGUACUCUACACCAGCCAGCACAGCGCCUGCUUCCUCUGCAGCAAUGAGAAAAGACUGCCCACACUCUCUUCUCUCCAGUAAACACGGUUCUCCCUGCUAGGCUUGGCCCCCUGGCCCUUCCUGUGGUCCUCCUACUAACCAGGCUGAAGAAGAUGGAGACAAGACAAUAGUGAUCUUUACUCGUUUCAUCUAGUUUGCAAAAUGAGACCACAGAUAGUAUGUUUAUGGACCUUGAUACUAUGAGUUGAUGGUACAAUGAGCAGAGUUCUGUGAUAAGUAGAUGUAAGGUACAAAUACAAACAAUAUAUACGACUGUCCUAAAGGGGUUCACACUGCAUUCUGGGCAGGGGAGGUUGUAUACUGCUCCCACUCCACCUUCCCCGCAAACAGAAGCAAUGGGACAGUAAAAGGGACUAGAAGAUAAGAGCCUAAUGAGCCCUGAACUGAAUGGACUAUGAGGGUUAUGGAGGGCUACCUUGGGCUGGGCCCUGGAGAACAGGUCAUCAUGAUAGCCCUUCUCACUUUCCUUUAAUGUUCAUGGAGAUACACUUUUUUUUUUGAGAUAGGGUCUCCCUUUGUUGACCAGGCAGGAGUACAGUGGUGUGAUCUUGGCUCACUGCAGCCUUGAACUCUCAGGCUCAAGCAACCCUCCCACCUCAACCUCCUGAGUACCUAGGACUACAGGCACGAGCUACCACACCCAGCUAAUUUACUUUUUUUUUUGGUUGAGACGAGGUCUUAUCAUAUUGCCCAGGCUGGUCUUGAACUCCUGGCCUCAAGGGAUCUUCCCACCUCGAUCUCCCAAAGUGUUGGGAUGACCAGUGUGAACCACCAUGCCUGGCCUUUUCUUUUGAGACAGUCUCGCUCUGUGGCUCAGGUUGGAGUGCAGUGGCACCAUCAUAACUUACUACAGCCUUGAACUCCUGGGCUCGAGUAAUCCUCCCACCUCAGCCUCCUAAGUAGCUUGGACUACAGGUGUAGAUUCACUUUUAAAUCACUUUUCUGCCUGUUAUUUUAAGAGAAAGCCCUUCGCUCACCAAGUAGGGUUCUCACUGGCAUAAGUAAGUUUUUCUGAAAAUGAGACUGAGCUUAGGGGCCACCUCUGUGAUUGGGUAAGUAAGCAGGAGCUAGAGUGAAAGAGGGGCAGAGAGAGCUAGCUCAUCGAAGAGAAGUGAUGGGCAUCUCAGCCCUCAAUCCCAGGCAAGGCCUGACCCUUUUCUGGAAUGGUCUCUGCCUUACCACACCUCCAAGACCCAGAUUGUAGGUAGGCUUUACCUAAUAGGAGUCCAACAAGUUCUUGCUAGGGAUGGGAUUGUGGGGGGGCACAUAUCUCCCUGUAAGAGCCACAGUGAGCUCUGUUUCCCAUCUGCCUACUUAUUGCCCUCGUGGGCCUGAGCUGGGGUGUAGAUAUAUAAGGAGGAACAGAAACAGUAAUAACAGGAAGUAAGGAGGCACUGAAACAAUUCAAGUAUCUGGUCCUGGAGAUGAAAAGAGGAAAUGGAAAAAGAAAAGGCAUUGAAUGACAAGGGAUUAGAACCCUGUCCCUAGAGAAGUUCAAGAAGAGUUUGGACAACCAUUUUAUGAGAUGGCAAGUGUUGUGCAUGAGUAUGUGUUUGAGGUGGGGGAGGAAGUUGAAGCAAUAAGUUGGGCCAAUUUCCUAAAGUCCCUUCUGCCCCUGAGAUUCUCUGCUUCUGUGGUUCAAACAGAGGAAAUCUGGACAUUUGUCCAGCCACUAUUUUUGUAAUGGAGGUGGGACAGCCAGGGUUCCUGGAGUGUGCUGUGGAAUCGGCAUUUACACUUCUCUUCCAUCUCUAGUCUCAUUUCUGUAAUCUUCAUACAGUAUUACAGUAUUUUGUUUUCUAAAAUACCAGAUUGGCAGUAAGUGACAAAACUAGCAUCUCAUUGGUCAGGGCUUGUGGGGGAGGAAGGGAGAAGAAAGUGGAUUUCAAUGUAUUAACAUUUUAUUGGCUGAGAGGAUGUUUCUGAACCAAUUGAGUACCUUCCCCAUUGACUGUUGCUGGGGCCAAGCCAAAAUCAUUGGCACCACGAGAAACCAGAUGACAGCUGGAGGAAACCACGAGUGCUAAAAAUGCUCAGAAAGAGGGGGGUCAGGGAAGGCGGGGGAGCAACAACACUGAACAACUUCCCCAGGCAGGAUCUUACAUGGGGACAGACCCAGGGUACUUAAGUAGCAUUAGGAAGGAAAGGGAGGGGAGGAAGUAGAUUAAGUAUCCCUCACAGUCUUGGCACAACAAACAGGCACCAUACACCCACACCAACAGUGACACAUUGACAUAACACACAUCCAACUUCACAGAGACACACUAGCACAUUCUCUCUUUUUUUUAAAAUUUAUUUUAUUAUUAUUAUACUUUAAGUUUUAGGGUACAUGUGCACAAUGUGCAGGUUAGUUACAUAUGUAUACAUGUGCCAUGCUGGUGUGCUGCACCCAUUAACUCAUCAUUUAGCAUUAGGUAUAUCUCCUAAUGCUAUCCCUCCCCCCUCCCCCCCUGCCUUUCUUUUUCUUCUUUUUUUUCUUAAGACAGAUUCUCAUUCUGUCACCCAGGCUAGAGUGCAAUGGCGUGAUCUCGGCUCACUGCAACCUCCACCUCCCAGGUUCAAGUGAUUCUCCUGCCUCAGCCUGCCAAGUAGCUGGGAUUACAGGUAUGCACCACCAUGCCCAGCUAAUUUUUUGUAUUUUUAGUAUAGAGACGGGGUUUUCCAUGUUGCCCAGGCUGGUCUUGAACUCCCGGGCUCAAGUGAUCUGCCUGCCUCGGCCUCCCAAAGUGCUGGGAUUACAGGUGUGAGCCAGGGUGCCUGGCCAACACAUUCUGUUGAUAAUAUAGAUGCAAAUAAGUAGUAGGGAGCGGAAAAUGUAAGAAUUUUCACCUGAAAAUGGAUCUGAAGAGUAAAAGAUAUUAAUUGACCUAAUCGUGCAUUGAGAAUUGACUGUUUAUCCCAUUUAUUUGUUCAAUAAAUAAGCCAAUGGGUUGUAAACAUUGUAAACAUUCCACAGCAUGUGGAAAGGACAUGGAUUUUUGGAGUCAAAUUGAAUCUAAGCCUUGCUACUUACUUACCUGUAAUGAUGCAACCUUAAUUACUUGAUCUCUGUAAACCUCAGUUUCCUUACCUACAAAACGUUUGUACUAUUACCUGCCUUAUAGAGAGGUCCAGACUUAAGAAUAUGAUGAUGUAAAUGUUUGGCACUGUGUCUGGCUUUUAGUAAGUGGUCAAUAAAGGCCAGUUCUCCUUUCCUUA